AGUCUCUUCCCCAACUCUCCCCACCCCUGGUGCUCUCCGCCCCGCUUGCCUCCCGUUCUUCCCCGCCCGCUCCAUCCGGGUCGCUGACGGCUGUCUCUGGACUGGACAGCAGUGGCGUCCGCUUUUCUCUAAGGAACCCGGUAAAGUUUCCCAGGGGCCGGGGAGGGGAGCAGCGGAGCAGCGGCACAGACGCCGGAGGUGCCCUGGUGAUCGUCGCCACUGGCUGACAGAGGAGGGUCCCAGGAGCCGGAGACGUGCUUCAGCGACCGCGCUGCCUUGCUCUCUGGGCAGGGGCCGCCCCCCGUCACCUUGGGCUUCCCCUACCCUGAAGGGCUUGGGCGAGUUGUGGCCCCAGCGGGUUCGGGGGCGUGUGACGGCGUUAGGGAGGGGCAGGCCGGGCUGGGCGGAUGCAGGCCGGCCCGGCAUAGGGCGCUUUCUCCGCGCUUCCUGGGGGUGAGGGGCGUGGGGCGAGGGCAGGGCUGUGGCUCCCUGGCCCCGGGGCUGGAAUGUCUCAUCUGCCUGGGGAUGGGCUUCUCUCAGGUUGAGGCCGCGCACUGCCAAGCCUCGGCCGCCGGCCUCUGAAGCUGUUGCGAGCGGCCGGUUGCGGUAGUCGUCUGCUUGGCUGCGAGGUUGGGUGUGUGCAGAUGAUUUCUCUUUCCCAGUCCCCAUGAGCUGAUCUGGGUGCACGUUCAGGGAAAGACGGGACUAAACUGCUUCUCAUUUCCCUACCUGUUGCUGGCGAGAGGACGCCUCUGUGUUUUAAAGAAAAGGGUGGUUAAACCUCGCGCGCUGAAGUCGGGGUAUUUUCCUGUAUUACUCUUAUUUUGUUUUUAAAUAUGGGAAGACAAUGCAGAACUCUUGGGAAUUAUCGAGUUCUGAUACCCCAAAAGAAUGAAAUCAAACUUCUGUUAAUGGGAUGAUGGGUCGUGGAAUGGGACACCUUGGGCACUUGCUAACAGGAACAUAGGAAAAUUGGAGUUGAAACUUCGCAGGCUCUGUAAGAAUGUGGAUGACUGCUACAGAAUAAGGCUGACUUCCUGUAAUUAUGAUAUUUAGUAACGCGAUGUGUUUAAAAGUCUACGUAUGUAUAGAUGAAGUGGACUCUGUUAUUUGUGUCUUUCUUUACAAGUGAGGAAAUAUUCAGUCAGUGUGCUGGAAAGUUCUACAGAUUUCGCCAUCAGACUAUCCAUUCCUAUUCUUGAAAAAUCUGCAGUGCUGGAGUUAUUUGCAAUUCCCCCCCGCCAAUCUUUAAAUAAUUGUCUCAGAGAUAUAGAUAGAUAUAGAUUGCCCACGGGUGAUUUUUUUAAUCCCGGUUACCACUUGUAAUAAAAGAGGUUGAAUUUUGGAGAGAAUUGAUAUUUAAAUUGCAUGUUUUUUUUUCUGUAUUAUAAUUAUGCACAUUGAUUUAGUUUUAAAAUUAGUGAGGUUGGAAUGUUAGUAUUUUGAUUUGAAAUCUGGGAUCUUUGGAGGUGAUUUAAGAUUAUGGUUUGGUAAGAGAAUCUUCAUUUUCUCUCUGGGCUAAAGAGUAAUUGGGAGAGUCGUUUAAAUUGUGGAAAAUUGCUUUAAAUUUCCAUUAUUGGUUUUAUUUCUGUUACAGAUAAGAACUCCAUUUUCUGUUGAUGUGGAGGUAGGUAUUAGAAAGCUUAAUUAUACUAGGAUUGCAAGGUUAUGUUUCUGCAGUUGGCUAAAUUUUGCACUGUGUAUAUUUGCUUUUUGGGCAGAGGAAAGAUGUCUUAUUUCUUGUUCCCAUUGAAAUUAUUUAAAGCAAAAAGUAGAAAAAAUUGUGAUUAAUUUCAUCAAGGUACUUAUUCCUAUUAGUUUAGUCUAUCACAAGAUAACCAGAAGUCAAAACUAGUUAAUAUGUUUUAAAUUUUGCAAAGGAUCAUAGAAAGUGUCAUAUUUUCCCUAAAAAUUUCUGUAUGAUACAUUUUAAAAAAUACAACUGAUUGGUUUUUGAAACUGAAUGAUACUUAUGUAGCAUGUUAUAAAGUAUAUUUAAUGUUUACCAUGUAGCAAUUAUUGUAGCCUAGCACUUGAAAGAGCAAUUAUACAUCCUUUUUUCUUUGAAGUCAUAUUAACUUCUUUCUAUUUCCUCAGACAUAGGGUACCUCCAACUUUCCGGGGUUUCAGAAGAGAAUUUUUUAUUGAAACUGGAAGACCAAAAUAAUUACAAGCAUGUUGUGCUGGGGAAAUGCAUCCUUUGGGCAGCUAGGUUUGGGUGGAAUUGAUGAAGAAAUUGUACUAGAGCCCAGAAAAAGUGACUUCUUUAUAAAUAAAAGGGUCCGAGAUGUAGGAUGUGGACUCAGACAUACUGUGUUUGUUCUGGAUGAUGGAACAGUGUACACAUGUGGAUGUAAUGAUCUAGGACAGCUAGGUCAUGAAAAAUCCAGAAAGAAACCAGAGCAGGUUGUUGCCCUGGAUGCCCAAAAUAUUGUAGCUGUUUCAUGUGGAGAAGCUCAUACGUUAGCGCUAAAUGACAAAGGCCAGGUGUAUGCUUGGGGUCUCGAUUCUGAUGGACAGCUUGGCCUGGUAGGAUCAGAGGAAUGCAUCAGAGUACCCAGCUGCUUCCCGAAAAUCAUGUGUGUCGACUCUCUGGUCAGAAUUUGCUCCGGACUCUCUUAUGGCAGAAUCAGAAAUAUUAAAAGUUUGUCAGAUAUCCAGAUUGUACAGGUUGCUUGUGGUUACUAUCAUUCACUUGCACUUUCUAAAGCAAGUGAAGUCUUCUGUUGGGGACAGAAUAAAUAUGGCCAAUUGGGUUUAGGUACUGACUGUAAAAAGCAAACUUCACCGCAGCUGCUUAAGUCUUUGCUUGGAAUCCCUUUCAUGCAAGUUGCAGCAGGAGGAGCCCAUAGUUUUGUACUCACCCUUUCUGGAGCUAUCUUUGGAUGGGGACGCAACAAGUUUGGUCAGCUAGGUCUUAAUGAUGAAAAUGAUAGGUAUGUUCCUAAUUUACUAAAGUCACUAAGAUCUCAGAAAAUAGUUUAUAUUUGUUGUGGAGAAGAUCAUACUGCUGCUCUAACCAAGGAAGGUGGAGUGUUUACUUUUGGAGCUGGAGGGUAUGGUCAGUUGGGCCAUAAUUCUACCAGUCAUGAAAUAAACCCAAGGAAAGUUUUUGAACUUAUGGGAAGCAUUGUCACUGAGAUUGCUUGUGGACGGCAGCACACUUCUGCUUUUGUUCCUUCAUCAGGACGAAUUUACUCUUUUGGGCUUGGUGGUAAUGGGCAGCUGGGAACCGGUUCAACAAGCAACAGGAAAAGCCCCUUUACUGUAAAAGGAAAUUGGUACCCCUAUAAUGGGCAGUGUCUACCAGAUAUUGAUUCUGAAGAAUAUUUCUGUGUAAAAAGAAUUUUCUCAGGGGGAGAUCAAAGCUUUUCACAUUACUCUAGUCCCCAGAACUGUGGGCCACCAGAUGACUUCAGAUGUCCCAAUCCGACAAAGCAGAUCUGGACAGUGAAUGAAGCUCUAAUUCAGAAAUGGCUGAGCUAUCCUUCUGGAAGGUUUCCUGUGGAGAUAGCCAAUGAGAUAGAUGGAACGUUUUCUUCCUCUGGUUGCCUAAAUGGAAGUUUUUUAGCUGUUAGCAAUGAUGAUCACUAUAGAACAGGUACCAGAUUUUCAGGGGUUGAUAUGAAUGCUGCUAGGCUUUUAUUCCACAAACUUAUACAACCUGAUCAUCCGCAGAUAUCUCAGCAGGUGGCAGCUAGUUUGGAAAAGAAUCUUAUUCCUAAACUGACUAGCUCCUUACCUGAUGUUGAAGCAUUGAGGUUUUAUCUUACUCUACCAGAAUGUCCCCUGAUGAGUGAUUCCAACAAUUUCACAACAAUAGCAAUUCCCUUUGGUACAGCUCUUGUGAACCUAGAAAAGGCACCACUGAAAGUACUUGAAAACUGGUGGUCAGUACUUGAACCUCCACUAUUCCUCAAGAUAGUAGAACUUUUUAAGGAAGUUGUGGUACAUCUUUUGAAACUCUACAAGAUCGGUAUUCCCCCUUCUGAAAGAAGAAUUUUCAACAGUUUUCUUCAUACUGCAUUAAAGGUUUUAGAAAUACUACAUAGGGUAAAUGAGAAAAUGGGACAGAUUAUACAGUAUGAUAAAUUUUAUAUACAUGAAGUACAAGAAUUGAUAGACAUAAGAAAUGAUUAUAUCAACUGGGUCCAACAGCAGGCCUAUGGAAUGGAUGUCAACCAUGGAUUAACUGAGUUGGCAGAUAUCCCUGUUACAAUCUGUACAUAUCCAUUUGUAUUUGAUGCCCAAGCAAAAACUACUCUGUUACAGACCGAUGCAGUCUUACAGAUGCAGAUGGCUAUUGAUCAGGCCCACAGGCAGAAUGUCUCCUCUCUUUUUCUCCCAGUGAUUGAAUCUGUGAAUCCCUGCUUAAUUCUAGUGGUGCGUAGAGAAAAUAUUGUAGGAGAUGCAAUGGAAGUCCUUAGGAAAACAAAGAACAUAGAUUACAAGAAGCCACUCAAGGUUAUAUUUGUUGGAGAAGAUGCUGUGGAUGCAGGAGGGGUGCGCAAAGAAUUUUUCUUGCUCAUCAUGAGGGAAUUAUUGGAUCCUAAAUACGGCAUGUUUAGGUAUUAUGAAGAUUCCAGGCUCAUUUGGUUUUCUGAUAAGACAUUUGAAGACAGUGAUUUGUUCCAUUUGAUUGGUGUUAUCUGUGGCUUAGCAAUUUAUAAUUGUACCAUUGUGGACCUCCAUUUUCCUUUGGCUUUAUAUAAGAAACUACUGAAAAAGAAGCCAUCCUUGGAUGAUUUGAAAGAACUAAUGCCUGAUGUUGGGAGAAGCAUGCAACAGUUACUGGAUUAUCCAGAAGAUGACAUAGAGGAAACAUUUUGUCUUAAUUUUACGAUCACAGUUGAAAACUUUGGUGCAACAGAAGUGAAAGAGCUGGUUCUAAAUGGUGCAGACACAGCUGUUAACAAACAAAAUCGGCAAGAGUUUGUCGAUGCUUAUGUGGAUUACAUAUUCAAUAAAUCAGUGGCUUCCUUAUUUGAUGCUUUUCAUGCGGGCUUUCAUAAGGUCUGUGGAGGAAAAGUCCUUCUGCUCUUUCAGCCUAAUGAACUACAAGCAAUGGUCAUUGGAAAUACAAAUUAUGAUUGGAAGGAACUGGAAAAGAAUACAGAAUACAAAGGGGAAUAUUGGGCAGAACAUCCUACGAUAAAAAUUUUUUGGGAAGUAUUUCACGAAUUACCAUUGGAAAAGAAGAAACAGUUUCUGUUAUUUUUGACAGGUAGUGAUCGCAUUCCUAUUCUUGGUAUGAAGAGUCUGAAACUAGUCAUCCAGUCCACAGGAGGUGGUGAGGAGUAUCUCCCAGUUUCCCAUACUUGUUUUAAUCUUCUGGAUCUUCCAAAAUAUACAGAAAAAGAAACUCUACGCUCUAAACUGAUCCAAGCUAUUGAUCACAAUGAAGGCUUCAGUUUAAUAUAACUUUGGAGUUAUAACUAUUCAGUUUAGUGCAAAAGCAUUAAACUAUUUGUGUUUUUCUUGUGGUGAUGAAUUCAGCAAGGUGACAGAGGUACUAUUAUAAUUCUUACUUGCAGAAUGUUCAAUCUACGAGUGUUCAUGGAAGCCAAAAAAUAUUAAAGGAAAAUGAACAAACUGUUAAUAUUAUUGUACAGAACCAUGGAUUUUUUUUGACCAUCUUCUAAUAAACAUAGCAAGUAUUAUGAAUACAUUAAAGUUUUACUAACAUGAAUUUUAAGAGUUUGCAUAUUUCAGAAAUGAUCUGGUGUGAGUGCAUGGAAAUAUUGCUUAAUUUUUCUUCAAUCAUUGAGUGAAAAACCUUUAACUUUGGCCUGCAAUAGUCAUUUGAUUAUUUUUUCAUUUUGUAAAUAAUGUUAAGUUUUGUAAUAAAAUAGUUAUGUUCUGAUACCAGUACAGUUUCUAUGGUUGUAAUUGAACUUGAACAGACUUUUAAAGGUUAAAAAUUAUGAUUUAAAUCUUACUCUGAGACUCUAUAAAAAGAAAAAAAAGGUAGCAUGGUGGAAACACUAUCUUUUCUUUUUUGCUAGAAUAAGUGUCUUUGUGCAAACCUAAAUCACAGAUAGGGAAUAUACUACAUAACCUGCAGUUCUUUUCUUUGUGAAUCCUGACACACUGAUAGAUGGGGGAUUGUCGAUCAGAGAACUUAUUAAUAUUUAGUACUGGAAGAACUCUGUCUCCACAGUUGCCAGUAAUAAAAAGAAACAUUGGCUACUAUGAGCACCAAUCACUGGGUUAUAGCUUUCAAAAUUAUUGAUGCUGCAGUGCUUUAGAGCUAUUUCCUUGAAUUUAAGAAACAAAUCUUAACAGUUUUAUGGUGCUGAUGCUUAGUUGUCUCAUGCCAUUAAAUUGUAAAAGUGAGUUGAUGCAAUACAUGUGACUUUCUGCUAUAAUGCAAAUAUUUAUUUUUUAAAUUUAUUUUAAAAUGCCGUGAAAACUGUUUAAUAAAGAUUUAUUGUUUUAAUAUUUAAA